CCCUGCUCGGCGCUGCCCGCCCAGUUCCUGUUCCCAGACUGAGGCCCAGCCCCCUUCGCCCGUUUCCAUCACGAGUGCCGCCAGCAUGUCUGACAAACUGCCCUACAAAGUCGCCGACAUCGGCCUGGCUGCCUGGGGACGCAAGGCCCUGGACAUUGCUGAGAACGAGAUGCCGGGCCUGAUGCGUAUGCGGGAGCGGUACUCGGCCUCCAAGCCACUGAAGGGCGCCCGCAUCGCUGGCUGCCUGCACAUGACCGUGGAGACGGCCGUCCUCAUUGAGACCCUCGUCACCCUGGGUGCUGAGGUGCAGUGGUCCAGCUGCAACAUCUUCUCCACCCAGGACCAUGCGGCGGCUGCCAUUGCCAAGGCUGGCAUUCCGGUGUAUGCCUGGAAGGGCGAAACGGACGAGGAGUACCUGUGGUGCAUUGAGCAGACCCUGUACUUCAAGGACGGGCCCCUCAACAUGAUUCUGGACGACGGGGGCGACCUCACCAACCUCAUCCACACCAAGUACCCGCAGCUUCUGCCAGGCAUCCGAGGCAUCUCUGAGGAGACCACGACUGGGGUCCACAACCUCUACAAGAUGAUGGCCAAUGGGAUCCUCAAGGUGCCUGCCAUCAAUGUCAAUGACUCCGUCACCAAGAGCAAGUUUGACAACCUCUAUGGCUGCCGGGAGUCCCUCAUAGAUGGCAUCAAGCGGGCCACAGAUGUGAUGAUUGCCGGCAAGGUAGCGGUGGUAGCAGGCUAUGGUGAUGUGGGCAAGGGCUGUGCCCAGGCCCUGCGGGGUUUCGGAGCCCGCGUCAUCAUCACCGAGAUUGACCCCAUCAACGCACUGCAGGCUGCCAUGGAGGGCUAUGAGGUGACCACCAUGGAUGAGGCCUGUCAGGAGGGCAACAUCUUUGUCACCACCACAGGCUGUAUUGACAUCAUCCUUGGCCGGCACUUUGAGCAGAUGAAGGAUGAUGCCAUUGUGUGUAACAUUGGACACUUUGACGUGGAGAUCGAUGUCAAGUGGCUCAACGAGAACGCCGUGGAGAAGGUGAACAUCAAGCCGCAGGUGGACCGGUAUCGGUUGAAGAAUGGGCGCCGCAUCAUCCUGCUGGCCGAGGGUCGGCUGGUCAACCUGGGUUGUGCCAUGGGCCACCCCAGCUUCGUGAUGAGUAACUCCUUCACCAACCAGGUGAUGGCGCAGAUCGAGCUGUGGACCCAUCCAGACAAGUACCCCGUUGGGGUUCAUUUCCUGCCCAAGAAGCUGGAUGAGGCAGUGGCUGAAGCCCACCUGGGCAAGCUGAAUGUGAAGUUGACCAAGCUAACUGAGAAGCAAGCCCAGUACCUGGGCAUGUCCUGUGAUGGCCCCUUCAAGCCGGAUCACUACCGCUACUGAGAGCCAGGUCUGCUAAUCUGUCACAUGUGUGACACUGACCGGGUACCCACAAUGAAAGAUGAUGUGUCUCCUGCUCCACCCCCAAUACCCCAAUACUCCACUCCUGAUAUCUGGGCUGCCCCCAUCAAAGCUUCAUGGAGAAAGAAGGAAUUGGCCAAGGGUCCUGCAGUAUCCAGGCCUAGCCCUGGUUGGAUUUUUUCCAGGAAAGAGAUGGGAAGAUGAGGCCUGUGGUUGGUGGAAAGUGGCUGUUUAUGGAGCAGUGGACUGAACUUUGGAAAGAGGAGCCCUGGGUCUGCUGCUGACUCACUGUGUUCCCCGCAGGGACAGAAAUACCUACUUCAGAUGGCUGUCUUGACGCUCGAAUGAUAGAACAUUAGUGAGGAGUUUUUAUGCUGAGUUUUUUUUUUUUUUUUUUUUUUUUUGAGAUGGAGUCUUGCUCUGUCGCCCAGGCUGGAGUGCAGUGGCGCGAUCUCGGCUCACUGCAAGCUCCGCCUCCCAGGUUCACGCCAUUCUCCUGCCUCAGCCUCCCGAGUAGCUGGGACUACAGGCGCCCGCCACCGUGUCCGGCUAAUUUUUUAUAUUUUUAGUAGAGAUGGGGUUUCACCGUGGUUUCGAUCUCCUGACCUCGUGAUCUGCCUGCUUUGGCCUCCCAAAGUGCUGGGAUUACAGGCAUGAGCCACUGUGCCCGGCCUUUAUGCUGAGUUUUAAGGGCUGUAUGAGACACCAGGUGGUGGGAGGGAGCUGUUUUGAGAGCAGGGAAUUUAGGAUACUUAGGAAAUUAGAAAAUUAGAGAAGUCAUAGGAUCUUGGAACUAAGGGAGAACCUUAGAGUCCUGUGGAGCAGAACCCAGCAUUUGUAUGUGGAGAAACGGAGGCCCAGAGAAGUUGUGACUUAUCCGGGUCACUCUGCAGGUCUGGGUGUCCCACCCGAGUCCAUGUCAGGGCUCUUUCUGCACACCAAGCCCCAUGCCCACCUCUGUGUGACUGGCUGUGGUGGGAGGGGCCUCCUAGGCUAGAGGUGCUGGGAUCCCUUUUCAGUCCAGAAAUAAUGAGCUUAGAGGGUCUGGAAGUAGCAUGGACUAAAACCCAGGAAGGAUCCACAGGGACUGUUGAUGCCAGUGAGGACUCCAGGAAGCCGGAUCACGGGGACUGUUGAUGCCAGUGAGGACUCCAGGAAGCUGCUGUUGGGACAGCCCUGCUUUGGGAGUCUGAGGUUCCAGGAAACCCCAGGAAUCCGGAUUCUCAUCCCUGAGACCUACUCAGGACUAGCCCAGGGGACCGAGCUAGGAAACCUGCUUGAGGUGGUAGAGGCAGCCAGGGGUGUGCAGUGGUCCGGGCGGGCUUCGAUCAGUUCCAGGUUGGUUGCUUCUCCAAACUGGCUCCAAGACAGGCAUGUGGCUCAAGUUGGUCUGGACUCAAUCCCGGGACUUUAGGACUUUUGCUAGAAAUCUGGUGUGGUGCAGGAGCGACUCCAGGAUUCACUCUGUGGGCUGCUUGGACUCAGACUCCCCCAGGACUAGAGGCUGCUUCUCCCUGGUGGGAGGAGUUACAACCUUGCAAGGGUUCUAAAGACCCCCGGGUGCUGGGUGGUGGGCUUUUCCUGACAACUUCCAUAAGUUAUUGGAACCUAAAUUCACACUGCUUAGCAUCGUAAUAGUCUGAUCAACCCUGCUCAGUGUUGUCAUACUUGCCCUAUUACCAGGGAGAGAAAUAGAGAGGUGGGUGCCUCCCUAGAGUAUCCACCCACACUGUGUACUGAAUGCCCCUCCUCAACCUGUCUCUCGUGGGGACCUGCACCUGCUUUUCCUACUAACUGCUGGCUUGUAUUUAUUCCCCUAAAGCCUGUUCCAUAACCCAGUGUGGUUCUUAGACUUGAGCAAACCUCAGAAACACCUGGAGGGCUUAUCCCCAGUCCUGAUUCUGUAGGUCUGGGGUGAGGCCUUAUAGUGUGCAUUUUAACAACGUCCCCAGUGUUUCCCAAUGCUGCUGGUGCACACCAAGUGUAGAAUUUGCCUCUGUGCCUGUUGCACAGUAGGUGGAGGUGGCAACUGUAAAAGAGACCCAGCUAUCCUAAAAACAGAAAAGGUACUGUCUUCAGUGGGGCUGCCAGGAUUGGAAGGAAUGUGAGCCUGUAGCUGCUCCUUUGCCCCCACGAAGGCCAGCUUGCCUUAGGAUGAAGCCAACACAGACCGGGUGCAGCAGCUCACACCUGUAAUCCCAGCACUUUGGGAGGCCAAGGUGGGCAGAUCACCUGAGGUCAGGAGUUUGAGACCAGCCUGGCCAACAUAAUGAAACCCUAGCUCUACUAAAAAAAAAAUAGAAUAAAAAAAAAAAUUAGCCGGGCAUGGUGAUGCACGCCUGUAAUCCCAGCUACUCAGGAGGCUGAGACAGGAAAAUCACUUGAACUGGGAGGUGGCAGUUAGAGUGAGUUGAGAUCACACACUGCACUCCAGUCUGGGGGACAGAGCAAGGGCUCAUCUCAAAAAAAAAAAAAAGAAAGAUAUAAAGCCAACACAAUUGAGAGAGAGUGACACAUUCCAGAGAAUAUUUGAGUAGCUGAAUCUAGACAUGUUUUACACUAACUGGAUCUAGCCCCUUUUUAGUGAAAUGAACCCCCCAGAAAGUUACCUUCUUUCCCUAAACCCAUCUCAAUAGGUUGCUGUCUGACAAUUCUGAGUCUCGCUGUAGUGGAGAAGACAUUGAAGACACCAGGUUAUAGAAAAACAACAGAGAAAAGAAAACAGAGGGCCGGGUGUGGUGACUCAUGCCUGUAAUCCCAGCACUUUGGGAGGCCGAGGCAGGCAGAUCACCUGAGGUCAGGAGUUCGAGACCAGCCUGGCCAACGUGGUGAAACCCCGUCUCUACUAAAAAUACAAAAUUAGCCUGGCAUGGUGGAGCACACCUGUAAUCCCAGCUACUUGGGAGGGUGAGGUAGGAGAAUCGCUUGAACCCGUGAGGCGGAGGUUGCAGUGAGCGGAGAUCAAGCCACUGCACUCCAGCCUGGGUGACAGAGCGAGACUCCAUCUCAAAAAAAAAAAAAAAAAAAGAAAAUAGAGAACUUGGGCCAGGUCCCCUCCCAGCUGCACCAUGAAGGGGACUGGAUUCGCCCCCAAGACUGCCUUGUCCAAUCCCUUCAUGGUGCAGCUGGGAGGGAAUUUUGCCCAAGGUCAUACAGCAGUGAGGGGCAGUGCUGGAACAGGAAUUUGUACCACCUGACUCUUUUAAAGAGACAAAGUCUCAUUUUGUCAUCCAGGCUGGAGUAUAGUCACAUUCAUGGCUCACUGCAGCCUUGAACUCCCGAGCUCAAGCGAUCCUCCUGCCUCAGCCUCCCAAAUAGCUCAGACUACAGGCGCGUGCCACCACACCUGGCUAAUUUAAUUUAAAAUUUUUUUUUGUAGAGAUGGGGGCUCGCCAUGUUGCCCAGGCUGGUCUCAAACUCCUGGGCUCAAGCAAUCCUCCUGCCUCGGCCUCCCAAAGUGCUGGAAUUACAGGAGUGAGCCACCAUACCCCAGCCCCUCUUGAUUCUUUAUCAGUGCCCUAUCCUGUACCUCUCAUGGCCUCUUGAGUAAGUACUGACCCAAGAAAAGAAGAUGCAGCUGCUUCUCUCCAGAAGCUCCACUAGUGAGACUACUCCCUGGGGUGGUGUUGACAAGGUCUCAUUAGAGAGCUGGGGAGUCACAUGGGGAGUCUGUUGGGUACACCUCUUGGGCCGAGUCUCUUGCAAGGUGUUGGCUCUACGCAGGCAGAGUCCCCUCUGCCUGGUUUUCAGUGGCCUGGUGUUUAAGGGCCUAGGCUCUGGAAUGACAUGGGCUGGAUCUGAAUCCCCAUGCUGAGGUGUGAGGUCUAUCUAGACACAUUGCUUAACAUCUUUGAGCCCCAGUUCUCUUAUUUACAGUGAUACUUAGGUCAAGACGUUAAUUUGAUAGUCUUGGUGUCAUGCCUGGCAUGAAGUAGCUGCUCAAUAAAUAAUCACUGUUAGUAUGGCACUAUGAUAACUGCAGACCACACAGGCCUCGAGCAGUGAGCAGCAGCCCAAUAUUUACUAUUGCUCUGGUAGUCUAUACAGCCAUAGAGUCCACGAAUUCUAAAGAGGAGCUCUGGAAAGUGUGAAAGCCUCUGGACUCCAAUGAAGCUAUUUGCUGGGCUCCCCAGGCAAAAAGAAGGCAUAAUAAUUGUCAAUAUCAUCAUUCUCACCAUUAGAAGGUGCCACCUCCCAGACUCUACAACUCGUAUAUCCAGCUGGGAGAGCUUCUAUUUCUCUGCAGGCAAUCAAUUAAUAGAAACCUCCUUUCUGUAAUGAACAUGAAAGCAUUUGACAGUUUUAAAGGAUUUUACCAAUUAAACAAAAGUCAUUCCUUUUCCUCCUUCCUGAACCCAAUACCCGCUCCCAACAUACACACCUUCUACUCCUGGUACAUGGAAGAAGAAAGGGUAACUCGUCUACUCUAGACUCAUCUUAAAUUGACUACAGAUGGUUUGGCUAAUUCAGUUCAAAUUAAAUUCUUUUCUUGCCUAUCCUGUCCUCUUCGCAAAUGGGAAUUGGCCCUUGGAGUUAAAUUUCUUUCUAAAGUUCCUACUGUAUGACUGGGGUAAUUUCUCAACAAUGGCUGGUGAUGUUAGAUCUGUGGUUGCUCAAAAAGAUGGAGGGGCUGGCUGCAGCGGCUCACGCCUGUUAUCCCAGCACUCUGGGAAGUCGAGGUGGGUGGAUCAUUUGAUCACCGUUCUGGGAUUACAGGCAAUGAGCCACCACACCCAGCCUGAACAAGUCACUUUUGAUGCUACCAUUUCCAUGUUUACAAAGUGAAAAGUAAAUCAGUCAGAGUAUAUUAGUUGCAAACAACAGAAACAACUCUAGCUAGCCUGAGAGAAAAAAAAGGUAGAGGGUUAGUCUCCUGGAGAGAUUUGGGGACCUCAAAGGAAAGAUUAUACAAUGUGCCUCCAAAAAAAAAAAAAAAGGGUCACCACAAGGGCAAAUGCGUGAUUUAAUGGGGUUGGGACUUUCAGCCCCAUCCCCCAACCUCUGGGGAGGAGAGAGGGACUGAAGGUCAAGUUGAUCACCAAUGGCCAAUGGUUUAAUCAAUCAUGCCUACAUAAUGAAGCCUCCAUAAAAACCCAAGAGGACAGGCUUCAGAGAGCUUCCUGAUAGCCAGACAUGCUGGGGUUCCUAGAAGGUGGCAGGCCCAGGGAGGACGCAGAAGCUCUGCACCCCUUCCCAUACCUCACCCUAUGCAUCUCUUCAUCUGCAGCCUUUGUAAUAGCCUUUAUAAUAAACUGGUGUGUUUCCCUGAA